AUUCGGCAGCUCCAGUUCAGCUCGCUCGGCGCACCCACGCCUCGCUGCCCCGCUUCCUGCCCUCAACCUGGGCAUGCGCCCCCCACCCUUCCGGCCCCCCAGAACCCGCGCCAUCCCCCGGAGCCUCCCCAGAGCUGGCCGCGCAGGAUGGGCGCCCUCAGGCCCACGCUGCUGCCGCCUUCGCUGCCGCUGCUGCUGCUGCUAAUGCUAGUUCCAGCUUCCUUGCCUCAGGAGAAACCAGGUUCCAUGGAGACUGAUCCUGGGAUCUCCAAGCACCUUGUGCCUGCUGUGGUGGGUGUUCAUGGUGGGGUGUUCUGGGCCAAUCUUGCAUGGAUGCAUGGGGAUAAUGACAGUGGAAUUGUUUUUGGCCUGAACUGGAGGGCUCCCUGUAGGAGGUGGUCUGGGGAAGAGUAUGGCAUGGAGACAGUGAAACUGCCAGUACAGAUGUUGAUGAGGCUGAAGCCCUUGAAAUGAGAGUGAAGCGUGGGGGUGGGGAUGGUGACUUCAGAGCUGCUGUCGUCAAGGCAGAGGCUGAAGGUAGCCCCAGCUGCCUGUUUCUAGACCAGAGCUCCACAGUGGCACCAAGCAAAGCCUUCCCCUGCUGCAGGUCCCUGGGCCCUGCAGGGUUAGGAUGAGUCCUCUCCCUGGUCCCUGGGCAGGUGGCAGGAGGAUGUACAGAGAGGAAGGCGCUGUGGGGCCUGGGUUGCCUAGCACUUGGUGUGUUUUCCCCAGUGGGCAGCAUGGAGCAGGGAGGAGCCCAGGGAGGUGGGGAAGUGCUGGCCUGUGUUUGAAAAAGGAGCACGCAGAGGUCUGAGCACCCACUGCCUGUGGGCACUUACAUUCAUUUCACAAAUGAGGAAAAUGAAGUAACUUGCCCCAGAGAGCACAUUUAGUGAGUGUUGGGGCUAGGAUUUGAACACAGAUCUGAUUCCAAAGCAGGCCUCUUUGCUGUCCCUUUCCUUGCUGCGACUGAUACAGAGGAGGGGAGAGAGAGCUGUGUGGCAACUGAUUUCCUAAGGCUGUGGAGGUGACUUUCCCAUGGGCAUCUCCAAGCAUCAGCAGUUGUGGAGCCAGGAAAAUGGGAGGGGGCCUUCUGAGCAGUCUGCCCUGAGGCAGUCAGGGAAGGUGUCAGCUUGGCUGUCUCCACCGUCACUCUGAUUAUGAAACUUGCCUGGCCUGGGGCAGGGCUCUCCUGAGUCACAUACGCACUCACACAUGGUCAGAGCUGGAGCUCUUAGUUCUCCUCCAGUGUGGAAACUGAGGCCUAGGACAGAAAGAGACUGGAUCCCAGGCCACACAGCUGGGCAUGGGGAUGGUGCUGGAAUCCCACUUCCUGACUGGCAGCUGUGCCCUUAACAACAGACCAUGAGUUCUCCCUGUGACCCAGCCAGAGGAUGAAGGAAGGGGCUAGGAGCCCAGAAGCAGGGGUGGGGAAGUUCAGAGGAGCCGUUCUAGAGAAGCUGGAGGGUAGAGUUUGACCACAGACUCCUGGGCAUUUUCCUCUAGCUCCUGCAGAAAGUCCAUGGUAUCCCCCUGGGAGGCCUAAAAGUGACACUCUGGUUGGUGAGGUCAGUCCCUUCAGGCCUGGCCUUGGAGUUUCCCCAUCUUCCUCUCUGGUUUUGCCCCUCUGGAGGAGUGUGUGGAAGCCAUCUAGGGACAGCAUGAUCUUGGCUAACAUAUUAUACUUUUCCUGCCUUACCUUUCUCAUCUGUAAAAUUGGGAGAGGUGGGGAGGGGUGGCCUAGCCCUCUUUACAUUGAGGUUCUGUGAUCUUAUCUAGUGGGAGCUAUGGAAGGAAAGAAGGGAGGAGCUAAGCCCUCUAAGUCUGCCAGGAGUAUCUGCUGGGGUAGGGUUGGGCAUAGGGGUGGAGUAGGGUGAAGAAGAGAGGUUUGGCCUUUCUGAAGGGAGAGAGAUGAGAAGGGGCAGCUGGGGAUUUAGUGCCUCCCUACAGAAAGAGAGCCAUAUAUGUAAAUGAAUGCAUACCAUGUGCAAAUGAAGGCUUUUGUUAAGGAACUGGGGCAGGCACCUUCUGUAUCUGCUGGGCUAGCCCGGAAGGUUGGCAGGCACUGGAGGAGGGGAUCUUCUGCCCCCAAUGGCCAGGGCAGAGCCUGGAUCUUGCCCCAGAAGCCCCAGCUGCCUGGGCAGCCCUGUGGGGUGAGAGAAGCAGUGAGCUCAUGGCGCAGCUGGAGAGGGGAGGGCAUUGUGUGGUGAGAACUGACUGGGCCUGUGCCCUUUCCAGCUAGGGUCACUGGCUCCAUUGUCUCGCCCAGGUGACACAGCUGAGCCAACUAGCACUUCUGAGCAAGACUGCCAGCUCCCCUCAAGCAAAGGAGAGGGACAUGUAGUCUCAGAGUCCCCUAGCCAGAAGGCUCCCCUUGCCAGGUGCUGAGGAAGGAAUGGCAGACAUGGAGGUGGGUGAGUGGCAGGGACAGAUCAAGGUUCAGUUGGAACCAAGGCCUGGUUAGGUCAGGAAUCAGAUGUACUCCUUUCUGCCUUCAGGUGCUCUGCUUCUAGUCCGCCAGAAAUGGGAUGCAUCUGGAUGCCAAGGCAAUCCUGGGCCCAUGCCACCUCCUUGAGAUCCAGGAAUGGGAUGCUGGGCCCGGGAGGUGCUGGUCCCCGAGGGGCCCUUGUACCGCGUGGCUGGCACAGCUGUCUCCAUCUCCUGCAAUGUGACCGGCUAUGAGGGCCCUGCCCAGCAGAACUUCGAGUGGUUCCUGUAUAGGCCCGAGGCCCCAGAUACUGCACUGGGCAUUGUCAGUACCAAGGAUACCCAGUUCUCCUAUGCUGUCUUCAAGUCCCGAGUGGUGGCGGGUGAGGUGCAGGUGCAGCGCCUACAAGGUGAUGCCGUGGUGCUCAAGAUUGCCCGCCUGCAGGCCCAGGAUGCCGGCAUUUAUGAGUGCCACACCCCCUCCACUGAUACCCGCUACCUGGGCAGCUACAGCGGCAAGGUGGAGCUGAGAGUUCUUCCAGAUGUCCUCCAGGUGUCUGCUGCCCCCCCAGGGCCCCGAGGCCGCCAGGCCCCAACCUCACCCCCACGCAUGACGGUGCAUGAGGGGCAGGAGCUGGCACUGGGCUGCCUGGCGAGGACAAGCACACAGAAGCACACACACCUGGCAGUGUCCUUUGGGCGAUCUGUGCCCGAGGCACCAGUUGGGCGGUCAACUCUGCAGGAAGUGGUGGGAAUCCGGUCAGACUUGGCCGUGGAGGCUGGAGCUCCCUAUGCUGAGCGAUUGGCUGCAGGGGAGCUUCGUCUGGGCAAGGAAGGGACCGAUCGGUACCGCAUGGUAGUAGGGGGUGCCCAGGCAGGGGACGCAGGCACCUACCACUGCACUGCCGCUGAGUGGAUUCAGGAUCCUGAUGGCAGCUGGGCCCAGAUUGCAGAGAAAAGGGCCGUCCUGGCCCACGUGGAUGUGCAGACGCUGUCCAGCCAGCUGGCAGUGACAGUGGGGCCUGGUGAACGUCGGAUCGGCCCAGGGGAGCCCUUGGAACUGCUGUGCAAUGUGUCAGGGGCACUUCCCCCAGCAGGCCGUCAUGCUGCAUACUCUGUAGGUUGGGAGAUGGCACCUGCGGGGGCACCUGGGCCCGGCCGCCUGGUAGCCCAGCUGGACACAGAGGGUGUGGGCAGCCUGGGCCCUGGCUAUGAGGGCCGACACAUUGCCAUGGAGAAGGUGGCAUCCAGAACAUACCGGCUACGGCUAGAGGCUGCCAGGCCUGGUGAUGCGGGCACCUACCGCUGCCUCGCCAAAGCCUAUGUUCGAGGGUCUGGGACCCGGCUUCGUGAAGCAGCCAGUGCCCGUUCCCGGCCUCUCCCUGUACAUGUGCGGGAGGAAGGUGUGGUGCUGGAGGCUGUGGCAUGGCUAGCAGGAGGCACAGUGUACCGCGGGGAGACUGCCUCCCUGCUGUGCAACAUCUCUGUGCGGGGUGGCCCCCCAGGACUGCGGCUGGCCGCCAGCUGGUGGGUGGAGCGACCAGAGGACGGAGAGCUCAGCUCUGUCCCUGCCCAGCUGGUGGGUGGCGUAGGCCAGGAUGGUGUGGCAGAGCUGGGAGUCCGGCCUGGAGGAGGCCCUGUCAGCGUAGAGCUGGUGGGGCCCCGAAGCCAUCGGCUGAGACUACACAGCUUGGGGCCCGAGGAUGAAGGCGUGUACCACUGUGCCCCCAGCGCCUGGGUGCAGCAUGCCGACUACAGCUGGUACCAGGCGGGCAGUGCCCGCUCAGGGCCUGUUACAGUCUACCCCUACAUGCAUGCCCUGGACACCCUAUUUGUGCCUCUGCUGGUGGGUACAGGGGUGGCCCUAGUCACUGGUGCCACUGUCCUUGGUACCAUCACUUGCUGCUUCAUGAAGAGGCUUCGAAAACGGUGAUCCCUUACUCCCCAGGUCUUGCAGGUGUCGACUGUCUUCCGGCCCAGCUCCAAGCCCUCCUCUGGUUGCCUGGACACCCUCUCCCUCUGUCCACUCUUCCUUUAAUUUAUUUGACCUCCCACUACCCAGAAUGGGAGACGUGCCUCCCCUUCCCCACUCCUUCCCUCCCAAGCCCCUCCCUCUGGCCUUCUGUUCUUGAUCUCUUAGGGAUCCUAUAGGGAGGCCAUUUCCUGUCCUGGAAUUAGUUUUUCUAAAAUGUGAAUAAACUUGUUUUAUAAAAAGCAG